GCAGGCAGGCUGACAAUGAUUUCCUCAGUGAUUACGUACAGAGCGAGUCCCUGCGGGUUAGGGGCCCCCUCUGGAGCCAUCCUGAUGGCUUUGGGGGCCUUGCUUCCAUUUUCCAUUAUUAUGUGGACUACCGGAGCGACAGCGCAGUCCAAGACCUUGCAGGAUGUCUCGCCGCAAGCAAGCGAAACCGAGAUCCCUCAAAGACCCCAACUGUAAACUUGAAGACAAGACUGAAGAUGGAGAGGCACUAGAUUGUAAGAAGAGGCCGGAAGACGGGGAGGAGUUGGAAGACGAAGCUGUGCACAGCUGUGACAGCUGCCUCCAGGUGUUUGAAUCGCUGAGCGAUAUCACAGAACACAAGAUUAAUCAAUGUCAACUGACAGAUGGAGUGGAUGUUGAAGAUGAUCCGACUUGCUCUUGGCCAGCUUCCUCACCUUCUAGCAAGGAUCAGACUUCCCCUAGCCAUGGAGAAGGUUGCGAUUUUGGAGAGGAAGAAGGUGGCCCUGGGCUUCCAUACCCGUGUCAAUUCUGUGACAAGUCGUUUAGCCGCCUCAGCUACCUAAAGCACCAUGAGCAGAGUCACAGUGACAAACUGCCUUUCAAAUGCACCUACUGCAGUAGGCUGUUCAAACACAAGCGCAGCCGAGAUCGCCACAUAAAACUCCACACCGGGGACAAGAAGUACCACUGCAGUGAAUGUGAUGCUGCGUUUUCCAGAAGUGAUCACUUGAAGAUCCACUUAAAGACUCACACGUCCAACAAGCCAUAUAAAUGUGCCAUUUGUCGCCGUGGGUUUCUGUCCUCUAGUUCCUUACACGGACACAUGCAGGUUCAUGAGAGGAACAAGGACGGCUCUCAGUCCGGUUCCAGGAUGGAGGACUGGAAGAUGAAGGACACUCAGAAGUGCAGUCAGUGUGAGGAAGGCUUUGACUUCCCGGAAGACCUCCAAAAACACAUUGCAGAGUGCCACCCCGAAUGCUCCCCAAAUGAGGACCGAGCGGCCCUCCAGUGUGUCUACUGCCACGAGCUCUUCGUAGAGGAGACCUCCCUCAUGAACCACAUGGAGCAGGUGCAUAGCGGGGAGAAGAAGAACUCAUGCAGCAUUUGUUCUGAGAGUUUCCACACAGUUGAGGAACUGUACAGCCACAUGGACAGUCACCAGCAACCGGAGUCAUGCAAUCACAGCAACAGCCCUUCCCUGGUCACGGUGGGCUAUACCUCCGUGUCCAGUACGACUCCAGAUUCCAACCUCUCAGUGGACAGCUCAACCAUGGUGGAAGCUGCCCCGCCAAUCCCAAAGAGUCGAGGGAGGAAGAGGGCCGCUCAACAAACCCCUGACAUGACUGGUCCCUCGAGUAAACAAGCAAAAGUUACCUACAGCUGUAUUUACUGCAACAAACAAUUAUUUUCAAGUCUUGCAGUUCUGCAGAUUCACCUGAAAACUAUGCACUUAGAUAAGCCAGAACAGGCCCAUAUUUGUCAGUAUUGCUUGGAGGUCCUGCCCUCACUCUAUAACCUAAAUGAACAUCUUAAGCAAGUGCAUGAAGCUCAGGACCCAGGUCUGAUUGUUUCUGCCAUGCCUGCCAUUGUCUACCAGUGUAACUUCUGUUCCGAAGUUGUCAACGACCUCAACACUCUUCAGGAACACAUCCGAUGUUCUCAUGGAUUUGCAAACCCUGCAGCUAAAGAUAGUAAUGCAUUCUUUUGUCCCCAUUGCUAUAUGGGGUUUCUCACUGACUCUUCCCUGGAAGAGCAUAUUAGACAGGUUCAUUGUGACCUCAGUGGCUCCCGAUUUGGGUCUCCAGUGCUUGGGACUCCCAAAGAACCAGUAGUAGAAGUCUAUUCUUGUUCCUAUUGUACAAAUUCGCCAAUAUUCAACAGCGUUCUUAAACUGAACAAGCAUAUCAAAGAGAAUCAUAAAAACAUUCCCUUGGCCCUGAAUUAUAUCCACAAUGGGAAGAAAUCCAGGGCCUUAAGCCCCCUAUCUCCUGUGGCCAUAGAGCAGACAUCUCUUAAGAUGAUGCAGGCAGUAGGAGGUGCACCUGCACGUCCCACUGGAGAAUAUAUCUGUAAUCAAUGUGGUGCUAAGUACACAUCCCUAGACAGCUUUCAGACUCACCUAAAAACUCAUCUCGACACUGUGCUUCCAAAAUUGACCUGUCCUCAGUGCAACAAGGAAUUCCCCAACCAAGAAUCCUUGCUGAAGCAUGUUACCAUUCACUUUAUGAUCACUUCAACGUAUUACAUCUGUGAGAGUUGUGACAAGCAAUUCACAUCAGUGGAUGACCUUCAGAAACACCUGCUGGACAUGCACACCUUUGUCUUCUUUCGCUGCACCCUCUGCCAGGAAGUUUUUGACUCAAAAGUCUCCAUUCAGCUCCACUUGGCUGUGAAGCACAGUAACGAAAAGAAAGUCUAUAGGUGCACAUCUUGCAACUGGGACUUCCGCAACGAAACUGACUUGCAGCUCCAUGUGAAACACAACCACCUGGAAAACCAAGGGAAAGUGCAUAAGUGCAUUUUCUGCGGUGAGUCCUUUGGCACCGAGGUGGAGCUGCAAUGCCACAUCACCACUCACAGUAAGAAGUACAACUGCAAGUUCUGUAGCAAAGCCUUCCAUGCGAUCAUUUUGUUAGAAAAACACUUGCGAGAAAAACACUGUGUAUUCGAAACCAAGACACCCAACUGUGGAACAAAUGGAGCUUCCGAGCAAGUGCAGAAAGAGGAAGUGGAGCUGCAGACUUUGCUGACCAACAGCCAGGAGUCCCACAACAGUCACGAUGGGAGCGAAGAAGACGUUGACACCUCUGAGCCUAUGUACGGCUGCGACAUUUGUGGGGCAGCCUACACUAUGGAAACUUUGCUGCAGAAUCACCAGCUCCGAGACCACAACAUCAGACCUGGAGAAAGUGCCAUCGUGAAAAAGAAAGCUGAGCUCAUUAAAGGGAAUUACAAGUGCAACGUGUGCUCUCGAACCUUCUUCUCCGAAAAUGGCCUCCGGGAACAUAUGCAGACCCACCUAGGCCCUGUCAAACACUACAUGUGCCCUAUUUGCGGAGAGCGGUUUCCCUCCCUUUUAACUCUUACUGAACACAAAGUCACGCAUAGUAAGAGUCUUGAUACUGGAAACUGCCGGAUUUGCAAGAUGCCUCUCCAGAGUGAAGAGGAGUUUUUAGAGCAUUGCCAAAUGCACCCUGACUUGAGGAAUUCCCUGACAGGCUUUCGCUGCGUGGUGUGCAUGCAGACAGUGACCUCCACCUUGGAACUCAAAAUCCAUGGGACGUUCCACAUGCAAAAGACAGGGAAUGGGUCUGCAGUUCAGACCACAGGGCGGGGCCAGCACGUCCAAAAACUGUAUAAGUGCGCAUCUUGCCUCAAAGAAUUCCGUUCCAAGCAAGAUCUGGUGAAACUUGAUAUCAAUGGCCUGCCAUAUGGUCUGUGUGCCGGCUGCGUGAAUCUCAGUAAGAGCGCCAGCCCAGGCAUUAACGUCCCUCCCGGCACGAAUAGACCAGGCUUGGGCCAGAAUGAGAAUCUGAGUGCCAUUGAGGGGAAAGGCAAGGUGGGGGGACUGAAGACACGCUGCUCUAGCUGCAACGUUAAGUUUGAGUCUGAAAGUGAACUCCAGAACCACAUCCAAACCAUCCACCGAGAGCUCGUGCCAGACAGCAACAGCACACAGUUGAAAACGCCCCAAGUAUCACCAAUGCCCAGAAUCAGUCCCUCCCAGUCGGAUGAGGAUAUUGUCUUCUCUAUGACUGAAGAGACCAGCGCUCAUGCCAACACUACUGAGAUCUGGAAUCUCAGCAUAGCUUCACCGUGAGUUGAAAUCCCCAGCUAUGACUUGUGUGUAUGGCAGAGAGAUAAUGACUCAAAAGUAAGAUGCUAUGAGCCACCAUGCUGGCUUAGAGUAAAUUAAAAAGAAUAUAUAUAUUUGGGGAUAACAAAUUGGGUAGGGGUGGCUUUUUAAUGCCAUGUUGUCAACACUCACUGUUUUUCUUUGUCUUCUGGGUAGAGAGGAAAAUACUUCCUCACAACAGGAUUUUUAAAAAUCCCCUACAUUUAUUAAGCACCACAUGCCCAUUAUUCUGUUUAAAGACACUAUCCCUGAGUUUGAGGCCUACUCUCUGGGUUUCAAAAUCAAUGUGUGCGUUUUUUUUUUUCUCCUUAGUUUCAGAGUAGUUUUCUGCUUUCUUUGCCGUGACGAGUACAAAAAACAAGUUCAUUUAUAAUGAAAUCAUUUCAUAAGUCAUCAUUUCUUAGUAGCUGAGCAGAGGAUGGCUCAUUUUAAUAUUUCUUUAUGCUUUAUCACCUGGUUUCUAAAAGCUCUUUCCACUUCCCUACCUGCCCCUAUCUGGAGAUCCAUCCAAAUGAAAACCCCAGGGAGAUCCUUCUCCCUUCAGUUUGGGGUUACUGCAUUUUCCUUAUCUUGUCUCUGCACUCACACCCUGGCGGAGGCCCCCCUGUGGCUCCCUGCAGAUAGCCAUCAGUCAGCUGGCAGGGGCGGGCUGAGAAGACUGAGACAGAGCCUGGCCUCACAAAAUGUGGCAUCUGUGUGGCAGGCAAACUCCCAAACUUUGAAGCCACUUUCCCCCUUCUCCCCUCCCCAAGUAAAUCUGCACUUUUCUCUCAUUUAAAUACAUGAAAUCCUUUCAAACUGCUGAGGACAGCUGGAAGAACAUAGCUUUGAUUAUGGCUCAUAGCUCAUGGGUUGGAUCAAAUUGUUUCUUUUGAAACAAAUAUUAGUAGUUAAAAGCAUAUGAAAUGAGGGUUUUCCAAGUUUUUACUUCGGAAUUUUUUAAACCUAUAGAAAAGUUAAAGGACCAACACAGCGAACACGUAUGUGUGCCUGUGUAUGGGUAUCCCCAGGUCCUCCAGAUAAGAAUAUUUUGUAGCGUUUUCUCUCUCUCUGCACCCCUUUUUAAAAUCAACUUCAGCCACAUGAAAGAAAGUUGCAGGUAUCAUGACAUCUCCUAAGAAUAAGGGUAUUUUUUUGUUCAAUUAUGACAUCAUUAGCUAAAGCAAUUCACUAAAUUAAAAAAGGAAAUUAAGUAAUCCCAUAAUAUCGUCUGUAAGAGGUUCAUAUUUAGAUUUCCUCAGUUGUCCCCAAAAUGUCUCAUAUUUUUAAGUUUUUGAAUGAGAAUUCUGAAAACAUUAAGGCAGAAAAUUACUCUUCUCCUUUGUUUUUAUUUUGUAAUGCUUAACAUAUGCCUACAAGAGAUUGAUACUCAUGUUUAAUUUACAAAGUGUGUAAAGUUGAUUUUAAAUGACUGCAUUAGUCUGUGUGUCUGUGUGUGUGAUUUUGGUGUUGCUUGUGCAUUUUAAAUGAGGCAUAGCUGGACUCUCUUGUUUCUUAGUAGAUUGUUUAUGAAAGGGCAUAUGCCUGUGUCUUCUUAUCUGUUCAUGGUUUGUAUUUUCUGAUAUUUAUAAAUUGCUGUAAUUAUAAUAACAUCUAAGAGGAAAUAUUUCAAAAACGAAUGAGGACAUAUAAAUAGUAUUUACACAUUAAGUUGGUUAGAAUUACUCGAUGAGGAGAAUUUAUCAUUAAGGCUCGAAUGACACCUAAAAUCUUAGUGAUAUUUAGAAAGCCUAUCUUUAUCCUGCACUUACAUAGGAUAAUACUUCAAAUAUUUUUUAAAAUACUUGUUUAAGUUUUACAAUUGCAUUUUUAAAGUACCUAAUGACUAAGGGUCAAAAAUGACUAUGCAGUCGAGUACCUCCCUAUGAAACCUGAUUAAUAAGAGCUUAGAGUGGUAUGCUUAAUUGAUGAGAUAUUAGGAUUUAGUUUCAAAUAUUUCUUAGUGCCUCAAAAGUUCACUAAUUUGUUCAACAUUUUAAUCAUCGUUACUAUCGCCAUUUUUAAAUUCAUCAUACUAUUUGUUAUAAAAUUUUGUAUGAUACUCUCUACAAUUAAAUAUGUACAAUAUACCAUAUUAUUUAGACUAAUAUAGAAAAUUAUCUAAAUAUACACAAAGUUUUACAAAAAGAAGCCUAAAAAUAAUAUGUCAGCAAGAAAAAUACAAAAUAAAUACUCAUUUGUUCACAUUCUUUGUUAGCCAAGUUAAAUUUCUAUAAGUUCUCAUUUUGAGGAGUUUGUGCAUUUUUUCCAGAUUAGGUAAAAUGAAAUGUUAUUAUAUAAGUCUUUGUCAAAAGACAGGUGUAUCAUAUAGGAAUAAAUUUUAUCACAAAAAGAAAUGUGACAUAUAUGUCUAUUGACUUAGAUGCCCUAGGUAGCAAUUGAAGGACUUAGCAACAUAGGUGGUAUUUUCAUCUCUUCUUCUUGCUGAGGCUUGAGACUCCAGAAGUGAAAAGAAAAUCACAGGAGAUAAGAAAACCUGGAUACAUAGGUAUGGUCAAGAACAAGGUUAGAUUUUUCUGGACCAUGACUUAGAAUUACAUAGAAUAUCGGUAAACAUUUGUGUCCAUCUUUCAAAGACUAAAAAGAAUAUUAUAUGAUUGAGACUAGGUAGGAUACCUAAUUAAAAGGGAUUUAAACUUAAAUAUAAAUCUGGGGAGGAUAAGUACUAUAUAAAACCCUGCAAUCCAAAAAAUGGAUGAAAGACAAGGCAUGCAACACUAAAAGAAGGAUAAUUGUUGGUAGCUGUUAUGUAAUAGAGAGAUUUGAAAUCGAAGGCAGAUCUGAGUUUGAAUCCCAUUUCUUCUGCCUAAUGCUUUCUGAAUUUGUGAAAAAUGUUUUCUUUGUGCCAGAAUCCUCAGAUUAUUAAUCUAAAUUUGCAGUGAAGAUUUUGUUUUGAAUAAAAUAUUUUGGAGAACCUA